GCGCAGAUAGGGGUAGCCUGGAGGCCUGCAGUCCGCGCGGCCGCGGGGAGGGACGAGAGGGCCUGACGUACAGGUGAGUGCGCCUCUGCUGGCGCGCCGCGCCGGGCCCCCUGCCCGCGCCCCCUGUCACUUCGCCUCUCCGCCCCGCCCACGCUCCCGCCGGGUCUCCCCGUGAGUGUCCCGUGUCCUGCCAGCCUCGGGACGCCCCGCGAGCUCAGGGCUGCGCAGGGACUGUGGUAAUUGAGCGCGGCGAAGCCUUCCGUUCCUGCCUCCUGUCGCUCCUGCUGGCUCCGAAUGCAGACUGCGAACCCGGGGACGCAGUUGUCCAUUUCCUUUGACCUUGGGGACCCAGGAAGGUGCACUGCCCGCGGGGGUGGGGAGGGAGCGAGAGGAAUCCGACCCUGUCUCAGCCCACAGCCUCCGAGGUCUCCAAGUAAAGGGAAGGAUCUUUAGCUGCAUUAGACUUCAAAGCGUUUAGACCAGUUUCUCCAUCUUACGGAGCGGUGAACGGGCUCAGGAAUGUGGAGCGUUUCCUGGCGUCAAGCAGGUCAAAGUCAGCGCUGCUUUUUUUACAGACACUGCUUUUCUUACAGUCUUCGGUUAGUUCAGAUUGUAUACCUCUCCUGAAGAUGUCACCCAAAACCUCCUAUGGGAUUCUGCCGUGAUCAUCUCUCCACUCAUCCCACACCAACGCCAAAGAGAUCUUUUAAAAUGAACUUCCAUCAGAUUAUAAGCGCCAUGGCUAUGGCUAGUGUUAAAUUGCUUGCCGGUGUUUUAAGAAAGCCAGAUGCCUGGAUUGGACUCUGGGGUGUUCUCCGAGGGACACCUUCAUCAUACAAACUCUGUACUUCCUGGAAUCGAUACUUGUAUUUUUCUAGUACCAAGUUACGUGCACCAAAUUAUAAAACACUUUUUUAUAAUAUUUUCUCACUGAGACUCCCAGGGCUUUUACUAUCUCCAGAAUGUAUUUUUCCUUUUUCCGUAAGACUCAAAAGUAAUAUAAGGUCUACAAAAUCUACUAAAAAGUCUCUGCAAAAAGUAGAUGAAGAGGACUCUGAUGAAGAAAGCCAUCAUGAUGAGAUGAGUGAGCAGGAAGAGGAGCUUGAGGAUGAUCCUACUGUAGUCAAAAACUAUAAAGACCUGGAAAAAGCAGUUCAGUCUUUUCGGUAUGAUGUUGUCCUGAAGACGGGGCUAGAUAUUGGGAGAAACAAAGUGGAAGAUGCUUUCUACAAAGGUGAACUCAGGCUGAAUGAGGAAAAAUUAUGGAAGAAAAGCAGAACGGUGAAAGUGGGAGAUACAUUGGAUCUUCUCAUUGGAGAGGAUAAAGAAGCAGGAACAGAGACAGUUAUGCGGAUUCUCUUGAAAAAAGUGUUUGAAGAGAAGACUGAAAGUGAAAAAUACAGAGUGGUGUUACGGCGGUGGAAAAGUUUAAAGUUGCCUAAGAAGAGAAUGUCUAAAUAAAUGGAUUGCUUUUUAGCAAUAGAGCUGCUUUCUAGUGGUAAAGGAAGGGGUCACCUGAAAAAUAGGACAUUUUUAUUAAAAUAAAGUUCUCUUAGCGUUUGUGGAAUCUGCCGAGCCAUUUUGUGGAAAUUGGGAUCCAUAUCUGGAGACACUUCCCAAGGCCUGCCUCACCUCCACCCCCUGCCCACCUUGAUCCAUGCUCCUUUGACCUCCUCGUGUGAGAACCCCUUUGCCAGAGUGAGACGUGUGCAGAAUGAACUAAGCCCCAGAGGGUUUUAAUGGCUUGCCUGCUGUUUCCCACAUAAACUACCUCAGGAGUCACUGUAAAAUAAACUGGCCUUGUUGUCUUA